AGUCGCGGCCCGGAGCUGCGGAGCUCGGAUCUUCUCCCCCGUCUGGCCCGCUCUCGACCCGCGCGCUCUGCUGGGCCAUGGAGCCGGCCCCCGACGCCCAGGAGGCGCGCACUGUGCGCGAGGCGCUGGGCCGCUACGAGGCGGCGCUGGAGGGUGCGGUGCGCGCGCUGCACGAGGACAUGCGGGGGCUGCAGCGCGGCGUGGAGCGGCGAGUGGCAGAGGCGAUGCGCCUGGCCGGCCCCCUGGCGCGCACGGUGGCCGACCUGCAGCGGGACAACCAGCGGCUGCAGGCGCAGCUCGAGCGCCUGACGCGCCAGGUGGAGGCGCUGGGCUUGGCCAGCGGGAUGUCCCCGGUGCCCGGCACUCCCGGCACGCCCAGCCCCCCGCCCGCGCCCGGGGUUCCCGACCGCGCGCCCCGCCUGGGCAGCGCACGCUUCGCCAGCCACGCCACCUUCUCGCUGUCCGGCCGCGGCCAGAGUUUGGAUCACGAUGAGGCCAGUGAGUCGGAGAUGAGAAAGACCUCAAACUCCUGCAUCAUGGAAAAUGGGCACCAGCCGGGGGCAGGUCCAGGCGAUGGACCCCCUGAGAUUGCCCAAAACUUCUCAGCACCAGAUCCCCCCAGGCCUCGUCCUGUGAGCCUCUCCUUGCGGCUGCCCCACCAGCCAGUCACGGCCAUCACCCGAGUCUCUGACAGGUUCUCUGGGGAGACCUCAGCUGCGGCUCUAUCACCCAUGUCUGCUGCCACCCUGGGGGGCCUCAACCCAAGCCCCAGCGAGGUCAUCACGCCCUGGACUCCCAGUCCUAGCGAGAAGAAUUCCUCUUUCACGUGGUCUGUGCCAAGCUCUGGCUAUGGGGCAGUGACAGCAAGCAAACACAGCAAUAGCCCACCGCUGGUGACACCACCCCAGUCGCCCGUGUCCCCGCAGCCGCCAGCCAUAACUCAGGUCCAUCGGCAGGGGGAGCGUCGCAGGGAGCUGGUGAGGUCGCAGACGCUGCCCCGCACCUCGGAGGCGCAGGCCCGGAAAGCAUUGUUUGAGAAGUGGGAGCAGGAAACGGCGGCCGGCAAGGGGAAAGGCGAGGCCCGGGCCAGGCUGAAGCGGUCGCAGAGCUUCGGCGUGGCCAGCGCCAGCAGCAUCAAGCAGAUCCUGCUCGAGUGGUGCCGCAGCAAGACGCUGGGCUACCAGCACGUGGACCUGCAGAACUUCUCCUCCAGCUGGAGCGACGGCAUGGCCUUCUGCGCCCUGGUACACUCCUUCUUCCCCGAUGCCUUUGACUACAACUCCCUGAGCCCCACGCAGAGGCAGAAGAACUUCGAGCUGGCUUUCACCAUGGCCGAGAAUCUGGCCAACUGUGAGCGCCUCAUCGAAGUGGAGGACAUGAUGGUGAUGGGCCGCAAGCCGGACCCCAUGUGUGUCUUCACCUACGUCCAGUCGCUGUACAACCACCUGCGUCGCUUCGAGUAAAGCCCCUGAGCCUGGAUUGCCAAAGAGCAGCCCCAGGAAGAGGCCGGGGGUCCGCUUGCGAUUCCCCAGCCAGGAUGCCCCCAGGAGCCUUGCCGUUUGGUGUGAGCGCGCUGUUUGUUCUGUGGCAUGUGACGGCACUCCCCUUCGAGCCCAGCUGUGUUACUGAUUAAAAGUACUGCUGAGCUGUGGUCCGACAGCACUGAUCACAGCCAAGGGCUUGGAGGAAAAGGAAAAAUUAUGAGAGAGAGAGAGACAUUGGUGCUAAGUAAUGAUCUUCCUAAAGAAAUGCUUGUGUUUAUAGCUUCCAGAAUGCUAAUCUACAAUUUUCCCUCUGGUGAAUUCGAUACAUCGGCUUUACAGGGUUACAGUGAUUACCAAGUGUUUUUUUUUAUCAAAAUACCCAGAGUUUUUUACUUCCUCACGCGAUUGUAGGUUCCUCUCCUCCCUCCCUCUGGGCCACUGCCAGGAAACAGAGAGACCGCUUAAUCAGCAGCUUGACAAAGAAGACCUCAAGUCUUGGGAAGAAACAGUUUAAUCACUCCCAAGUCCUGGGCAACAGAUGACCUUCAAGUCACCUCCGCUCUCCGGGGAGAUGGGAAGGCUCUCCUCUCGGUCCCAAAGUCCUCCUGUUCUUCCCAGGAGGCCCCACAAGUGUUUGGCUAAGCACAGGCUCUCGGGAAUUUAACACUUUUGGGGAAGGAAUAGGCCCUUUGUGCUGAGAGAGAGUUUUUAUUCACAUCUUUUUUAGGGGAUUUGCUGCAGAUAUUUAUAAAAAGUAACUCCCUCUGUACCACUGACCCAUUUAUACAUAAAAAAGAUGUGUUGAAUUUUG